AGGGGCCCCAGUGGCCGCCGCGGAGCGAGGUUGCCUGGAGAGAGCGCCUGGGCGCAGAAGGGUUAACGGGCCACCGGGGGCUCGCAGAGCAGGAGGGUGCUCUCGGACGGUGUGUCCCCCACUGCACUCCUGAACUUGGAGGACAGGGUCGCCGCGAGGGACGCAGGUGGGUGCCCUUGAUCCAGCUCAGCCCGAUGGCAGAAGAGGUUGACAAAAAAGAAAGACACCUGUUGGGGUGGCCUGCCAGACCCAGGAGUGGAGGGCUCUGAGGGCCCGGGAAUUCGGACUCAGGACAGGGAUUCUCCAUGGCUAGGCCCAGAAACACAGGGUCCAACCACUCUCCAGCAGGGAGACCUGGGGGUGAAGGGGUGAGCCCUGCGCAGGUCUCUGUUCCUUGGUCUUCACUGGGCAGUGUGGAGAGGUGUGGCCAGGAGGAGCCCGCGUUUGUCCAGACCAGGGUCUACUCUGGCACCAGAGUGACCACCUCUGACCUCUCCUUUCCUCGUCCUGGGCCGGGAACGACACCAAAUGAGGGACAUGGAAAGGGCUGGAGUAACAAGAGUCAGGCAGAGCCUGAAGACUUGGGUGGAACAUGGGCCCUUCUCUGGAGAUCCUGGCCUCCCCCGUUCAGUCAGGGUGGAGUUGCUGACCUUAGUGGCCGGCCCAGCCAGGGGAAGGAGUGGCCAUCGGCAACCCCCACCCCAACCCCAAUCCCUGAGGCGCCCGCUCUGGCUCAGCCACUCUGACCCCUCCCUCAAAUUCCGAACCCUAGGUCUCAGGGAGGGCAGUGGGGCUGAGUGUCUGCCCCCAGGCACAUUCCUACCCUUCUCUUGGUCAUUUUCUGCCCCAGAGCUGGCCCACCUCAGCAAUGCGAGGGCUCCCUGGAUUCCUCUCCCGGGUGCCUUUCAGAUCCAACAGAAACAGAUUUUUUUUUUCCUGGAAAGCAGAACUAAGAGUGGGAUGAGGAGCAGGGGUGGGAAGGACUCAAAGUGAGAAGAAGGGGGCAAAGAGAGUCAGGCUUGGUGGCUGGGGUGGCUUCCAAGCCUCACUUCUCCAGUGUUCAAAGCUGAACUUCAGAUGGACUUCCCGGCUCUUCAGAAUGAGAGGCCUGUGGCUGGGGCAUGAGGCAGCCCCGGCUGCACCUCUCCUUCCCGCUUCCCCAGCUGGUAGAGACGCACAGGAAACAAGCCCUCACUGAACCAACUCCAGAUGCUGGCACCCAGAGUGGGUGUUACAUUGCCGGCUUCUUCUCUAGAGAUUAAACCGUCAACCCAUUUAGCUUAUCCCUUGGCCAAAAAGUGUAUGAGAUGUGCCUGGAUGUUCCCUAAAGAGCUUAUCUAAGAAGGGAAGAGAAAGCCGGGAGGCAAGUAGGACAGAGAGAUGACUGGGGAAGGUCUUGUGUCUGGAAGACCCAAGGAAGGGGCUUCUGGUGGGUCCUCAGAGAGAGUGUCUGGCGCAUCCUCAGUGGAGCCUUCCUCCUCUACUUUCUAGGCACCUCUGGGAGGGCAGGAGUGGGAGCAGAUGACAACCAUUUUAGAAGGAGCCCUCUGGCUGGGUGCGGUGGCUCACACCUGUCAUCCCAGCACUUUGGGAGGCCAAGGCAGGAGAAGCGCUUGAGGCCUGGAGUUCAAGACCAGCCUGUGCAAUUUAGCUGGAUCCCAUCUCCACCAAAAAAUACCAAAAUUAGCUGGGUGUGGUGGUGCACGCAUGUAGUCCCACCUACUCAGGAGGCUGAGGAAGGAGAGCCUGUGAGUUUGAGGCUGCAAUGAGCUUUGGUGGCACCACUGCCCUCCAGCCUGGAUGACAGAGUGAGAUCUCCAUCUCAAAAAAAAAAAAAAAGCCUUUUGUGUGUGCCUGAGCCGGCUUAGAAACAGUCCCUAGGUAGGAUUUGGGGAGGAGCUAAGAAGCCCCUACAGGGCCCAGAGGUGGGGACUGAGCCUUAGUUGGAGGGCUGAGGUCAGCCCCUGACCAUGUAGCCUCUACAGAUGGACAAGGCAGUGAUCCUCCCUGCUCCCACCCUGAGGAUCCUAAAGGGAUGGACCAGUUUCACCCCCUCCUCCAUAUUCUCUGAGCUGUCCUCCCAGCCCCAAGCUCUCUGGACACUGGAGAGGUAACCACCAGGCUUCUGUCCCUGCAGAGAGCACCCUCCACGCCCAGAUGCCUGCGUAGUUUUUGUGACCAGUCCGCUCCUGCCUCCCCCUGGGGCAGUAGAGGGGGAGCGAUGGAGAACUGGACUGGCAGGCCCUGGCUGUAUCUGCUGCUGCUUCUGUCCCUCCCUCAGCUCUGCUUGGAUCAGGAGGUGUUGUCCGGACACUCUCUUCAGACACCUACAGAGGAGGGCCAGGGCCCCGAAGGUGUCUGGGGACCUUGGGUCCAGUGGGCCUCUUGCUCCCAGCCCUGCGGGGUGGGGGUGCAGCGCAGGAGCCGGACAUGUCAGCUCCCUACAGUGCAGCUCCACCCGAGUCUGCCCCUCCCUCCCCGGCCCCCAAGACAUCCAGAAGCCCUCCUCCCCCGGGGCCAGGGUCCCAGACCCCAGACUUCUCCAGAAACCCUCCCCUUGUACAGGACACAGUCUCGGGGAAGGGGUGGCCCACUUCGAGGUCCCGCUUCCCACCUAGGGAGAGAGGAGACCCAGGAGAUUCGAGCGGCCAGGAGGUCCCGGCUUCGAGACCCCAUCAAGCCAGGAAUGUUCGGUUAUGGGAGAGUGCCCUUUGCAUUGCCACUGCACCGGAACCGCAGGCACCCUCGGAGCCCACCCAGAUCUGAGCUGUCCCUGAUCUCUUCUAGAGGGGAAGAGGCUAUUCCGUCCCCUACUCCAAGAGCAGAGCCAUUCUCCGCAAACGGCAGCCCCCAAACUGAGCUCCCUCCCACAGAACUGUCUGUCCACACCCCAUCCCCCCAAGCAGAACCUCUAAGCCCUGAAACUGCUCAGACAGAGGUGGCCCCCAGAACCAGGCCUGCCCCCCUACGGCAUCACCCCAGAGCCCAGGCCUCUGGCACAGAGCCCCCCUCACCCACGCACUCCUUAGGAGAAGGUGGCUUCUUCCGUGCAUCCCCUCAGCCACGAAGGCCAAGUUCCCAGGGUUGGGCCAGUCCCCAGGUAGCAGGGAGACGCCCUGAUCCUUUUCCUUCGGUCCCUCGGGGCCGAGGCCAGCAGGGCCAAGGGCCUUGGGGAACGGGGGGGACUCCUCACGGGCCCCGCCUGGAGCCUGACCCUCAGCACCCGGGCGCCUGGCUGCCCCUGCUGAGCAACGGCCCCCAUGCCAGCUCCCUCUGGAGCCUCUUUGCUCCCAGUAGCCCUAUUCCAAGAUGUUCUGGGGAGAGUGAACAGCUAAGAGCCUGCAGCCAAGCGCCCUGCCCCCCUGAGCAGCCAGACCCCCGGGCCCUGCAGUGCGCAGCCUUUAACUCCCAGGAAUUCAUGGGCCAGCUGUAUCAGUGGGAGCCCUUCACUGAAGCCCCUCUGCUUCCCCUGCGCCAUGCCUUCUUUCUUCUCCCUGGGGCUGGGUCAGGAGACAGCACAGGUGUCCAGGGCUCCCAGCGCUGUGAACUGAACUGCCGGCCCCGUGGCUUCCGCUUCUAUGUCCGUCACACUGAAAAGGUCCAGGAUGGGACCCUGUGUCAGCCUGGAGCCCCUGACAUCUGUGUGGCUGGACGCUGUCUGAGCCCCGGCUGUGAUGGGAUCCUUGGCUCUGGCAGGCGUCCUGAUGGCUGUGGAGUCUGUGGGGGUGAUGAUUCUACCUGUCGCCUUGUUUCGGGGAACCUCACUGACCGAGGGGGCCCCCUGGGCUAUCAGAAGAUCUUGUGGAUUCCAGCGGGAGCCUUGCGGCUCCAGAUUGCCCAGCUCCGGCCUAGCUCCAACUACCUGGCACUUCGUGGCCCUGGGGGCCGGUCCAUCAUCAAUGGGAACUGGGCUGUGGAUCCCCCUGGGUCCUACAGGGCCGGCGGGACCGUCUUUCGAUAUAACCGUCCUCCCAGGGAGGAGGGCAAAGGGGAGAGUCUGUCGGCUGAAGGCCCCACCACCCAGCCUGUGGAUGUCUAUAUGAUCUUUCAGGAGGAAAACCCAGGCGUUUUUUAUCAGUAUGUCAUCUCUUCACCUCCUCCAAUCCUUGAGAACCCCACCCCAGAGCCCCCUGUCCCCCAGCUUCAGCCGGAGAUUCUGAGGGUGGAGCCCCCACUUGCUCCGGCACCCCGCCCAGCCCGGACCCCAGGCACCCUCCAGCGUCAGGUGCGGAUCCCCCAGAUGCCCGCCCCGCCCCAUCCCAGGACACCCCUGGGGUCUCCAGCUGCGUACUGGAAACGAGUGGGACACUCUGCAUGCUCAGCGUCCUGCGGGAAAGGUGUCUGGCGCCCCAUUUUCCUCUGCAUCUCCCGUGAGUCGGGAGAGGAACUGGAUGAACGCAGCUGUGCCGCGGGUGCCAGGCCCCCAGCCUCCCCUGAACCCUGCCACGGCACCCCAUGCCCCCCAUACUGGGAGGCUGGCGAGUGGACAUCCUGCAGCCGCUCCUGUGGCCCCGGCACCCAGCACCGCCAGCUGCAGUGCCGGCAGGAAUUUGGGGGGGGUGGCUCCUCGGUGCCCCCGGAGCGCUGUGGACAUCUCCCCCGGCCCAACAUCACCCAGUCUUGCCAGCUGCGCCUCUGUGGCCAUUGGGAAGUUGGCUCUCCUUGGAGCCAGUGCUCCGUGCGGUGCGGCCGGGGCCAGAGAAGCCGGCAGGUUCGCUGUGUUGGGAACAAUGGUGAUGAAGUGAGCGAGCAGGAGUGUGCGUCAGGCCCCCCGCAGCCCCCCAGCAGAGAGGCCUGUGACAUGGGGCCCUGUACUACUGCCUGGUUCCACAGCGACUGGAGCUCCAAGUGCUCAGCCGAGUGUGGGACGGGAAUCCAGCGGCGCUCUGUGGUCUGCCUUGGGAGUGGGGCAGCCCUCGGGCCAGGCCAGGGGGAAGCAGGAGCAGGAACUGGGCAGAGCUGUCCAACAGGAAGCCGGCCCCCUGACAUGCGCGCCUGCAGCCUGGGGCCCUGUGAGAGAACUUGGCGCUGGUACACAGGGCCCUGGGGUGAGUGCUCCUCCGAAUGUGGCUCUGGCACACAGCGUAGAGACAUCAUCUGUGUAUCCAAACUGGGGACGGAGUUCAACGUGACUUCUCCGAGCAACUGUUCUCACCUCCCCAGGCCCCCUGCCCUGCAGCCCUGUCAAGGGCAGGCCUGCCAGGACCGAUGGUUUUCCACGCCCUGGAGCCCAUGUUCUCGCUCCUGCCAAGGGGGAACGCAGACACGGGAGGUCCAGUGCCUGAGCACCAACCAGACCCUCAGCACCCGAUGCCCUCCUCAACUGCGGCCCUCCAGGAAGCGCCCCUGUAACAGCCAACCCUGCAGCCAGCGCCCUGAUGAUCAAUGCAAGGACAGCUCUCCACAUUGCCCCCUGGUGGUACAGGCCCGGCUCUGCGUCUACCCCUACUACACAGCCACCUGUUGCCGCUCUUGCGCACAUGUCCUGGAGCGGUCUCCCCAGGAUCCCUCCUGAAAGGGGUCCGGGGCACCUUCACGGUUUUCUGUGCCACCAUCGGUCACCCAUUGAUCGGCCCACUCUGAACCCCCUGGCUCUCCAGCCUGUCCCAGUCUCAGCAGGGAUGUCCUCCAGGUGACAGAGGGUGGCAAGGUGACUGACACAAAGUGACUUUCAGGGCUGUGGUCAGGCCCAUGUGGUGGUGUGAUGGGUGUGUGCACAUAUGCCUCAGGUGUGCUUUUGGGACUGCAUGGAUAUGUGUGUGCUCAAACGUGUAUCACUUUUCAAAAAGAGGUUACACAGACUGAGAAGGACAAGACCUGUUUCCUUGAGACUUUCCUAGGUGGAAAGGAAAGCAAGUCUGCAGUUCCUUGCUAAUCUGAGCUACUUAGAGUGUGGUCUCCCCACCAACUCCAGUUUUGUGCCCUAAGCCUCAUUUCUCAUGUUCAGACCUCACAUCUUCUAAGCCGCCCUGUGUCUCUGACCCCUUCUCAUUUGCCUAGUAUCUCUGCCCCUGCCUCCCUAAUUAGCUAGGGCUGGGGUCAGCCACUGCCAAUCCUGCCUUACUCAGGAAGGCAGGAGGAAAGAGACUGCCUCUCCAGAGCAAGGCCCAGCUGGGCAGAGGGUGAAAAAGAGAAAUGUGAGCAUCCGCUCCCCCACCACCCCGCCCAGCCCCUAGCCCCACUCCCUGCCUCCUGAAAUGGUUCCCACCCAGAACUAAUUUAUUUUUUAUUAAAGAUGGUCAUGACAAAUGAGAAA